GGGAUCACGUGAGGUCAGGAGUUCAGACCAGCCUGGCCAACAUGGUGAAACCCCAUCUCUACUAAAAAUACAAAAGUUAGCCAGGUGUGGUGGCACAGGCCUGUAGUCCCAGCUUCUUGGGAGGCUGAGGCAUGAGAAUUGCUUGAACUCAGGAGGCAGAGGUUGAGUGAGCCGAUUGUGCCACUGCACUCUAGCCUGGGCGACAGAGCAAAACUUGGUCUCAAAAAAUUACAAGUUAUAGGCCAGGCGCGGUGGCUCACACCUGUAAUCACAACACUUUGGGAGGCCAAGGCGGGUGGAUCAUGAAGUCAGGAGAUCGAGACCAUCCUGGCUAACGUGGUGAAACCCUGUCUCUACUAAAAAUAAAAAAUUUAGCCGGGCGUGGUGGCGGGCGCCUGUAGUCCCAGCUACUCGGGAGGCUGAGGCAGAAUGGCCUGAACCCAGGGGGCAGAGCUUGCAGUGAGCCGAGAUUACGCUACUGCACUCCAGCCUGGACGACAGAGCGAGACUCCGUCUCAAAAAAAAAUUACAAAUUAUCAGGCCGGGCGUGGUAGCUCAUGCCUGUAAUCCCAGCACUUUGGGAGGCCGAGGUGGGCGGAUCAUGAGGUCAGGAGUUUGAGACCAGCCUGACCAACAUGGUGAAAUCCUGUCUCUACUAAAAAUACAAAAAUUAGCUGGGCGUGGUGGCAUGCGCCUGUAAUCCCAGCUACUCAGGAGGCUGAGGCAGGAGAAUCACUUGAACCUGGGAGGCAGAGGUUGCAGUGAACCAAGAUCACACCAUUGCACUCCAGCCUGGGCGAUACAGCGAGACUCCUUCUCAAAAAAUAAAAAAUAAAAAUAAAAAUUAUCCUGCCAAGGAGAGUAACACUCAAAAACUACAAUGAAACAAGAAUUUGCAAUUUGUAAGCAUCUAGCUUUUGCCAGGCACAGGUGAAAGAAGUUUAGGGAAGCCUCCCUUAGAUUAUUACCUUUUUUCCUAGGUAAUAACCAUCUUCUUCUAUAAGGACAGAGUGAGACUUUGAGAGGUAAGAAAUGAGUUGAGGCCAAAGUUCUACAAGACAUUAAAGGAGCCUAGUGGAAAAGUAGGUCCUAAGUAGGAUAGACCAGAGGGCUCAGGAAAUUAGUUCCAGCUAUCAAAUCAUGAUAGCUACAAUGCCCUGGGCACUGAUAUCAUGUAUGGCUUGUGGUGGUUUAAAACAUGCCUACACAUUCCUUGACAUUCCUCCCACAUAGAGGUGGAGUCUAAGUUCCUUUGCUUUGAAUAUAGGGUAGCCGUGCUGACUCCUUUCUAAGGAACAGAAUGUGGCACGUGGUAGAACUGAUUCCAGGGCUAGGUUAGGAAAGGCAAUACAGCAACUAUAUGGCUUUCUUGUUCGCUCUCUGAACACUUGCCCUUAGAAUCCAGCCCUGAUAUUUCAAGGAAGCUCAGACACAGGGAGAGGCCAUGUGUAAGUGUUCCAGGGACAGCUCUAAUGGUCCCAGGUCCUAGCUGACAGCCACCAUCAACCACCAGACAUGUACGCUUUUACGGGACCCUCAGCCCCAGCCUUUGGGCUGCCCCCACUGGUGCUGAAUGGAUCAGAAACCAGCCGUCCCAGCAGGAACCAGCCCAUUUUGCAGAUUUGAGAGCAAAAUAUAAUUGGAAUUCUGGGGUGGUUUGUUACGUAACAGUAGGUAACCAGAAAUCCAUAAUUUCCGGGUUUCUAGUAUUUUCUUUUUCAAGAAAGCUCAGGUGUGGUGGCUCAUGCCUGUAAUCCCAGUGCUUUUGGAGGCUGAGGCAGGAGGAUCACUUGAGGCCAGGAAUUUGAGACCAGCCUGAGCAACAUAGCAAGAUCCCGUCUCUGCAAAAAAUCGUUAAAAAUUAGCCUGCUGUAGUGGCAGGAGCCUGUAGUCCCAGCUAUUUGGGAGGCUGAGGCUGGAGCAGUGAGCUAUGAUUGUGCCAUUGCUUUCCAGCCUGGAUGACAGAGCAAGACUUCAUCACCCCCAAAAUAAAAUAACCAGAGCAGUGUUUUUAAUGUUAUCUUUAAUUCCCUCUGCAAGCCUAAAAAGUAGGUAUACUGCGAUCCCUUUCGGAAAAAUGAGGAAAGGGAGAUCCAGGUGGUGAAAUGCCUGGCUCAGGUUUCACACUAAUUGGCAGGGUCAGGAUUUAGCAGCUUCAAAGAACGGGCCUUCUCCACUACUCCAGGGAGUCUCCAAGACACUAAAGGGGAUUAGACCUGUUUCCCACAGCUUUAGGAAGAAUUUGGAUUCCAAAAACAGCUUGAUUGUUAAAAUAAUAACAUCUGUAUUAUCACCUGCAACGUGUCUCUGUAUAGGCUUAAAAAGGCUCAGCAGCUUUAUGGGUUAUAUAUGGUUUUUUACCCACCUUAUCCUGUUUAAUCUUAACUGCCCCAUGAGCAGGUUAUAUCAUCUUCGCAAUUUCACAGGUAAAACUAAGAAUCAAUAGACUAACUCUCCAUAGCUUGUAGGAGGUGGCAGAGAUGAGAAUGCAAACUCAGGCCUGAUGUGCAAGUGUUUCCCUCUGCCUCUUGCCUGUAAAAAAACAGUUUGUAAGAAACACACUUUAUUCAGUAAUACAAACGAAAAGUUUUCUGUUGCCAAGAUUCACAAGAAGGGAGCUGAGUUAGUGGUCACUCACUGCCCAACACCCUAAUUUCACAAGUGAAGUGAAGUUCCAACAAAGUAGGCCUCUUGGAAGAAAUGUAGACGUUGCUGUCCUUUAACCAGGAAAAUUGCGUUCUCGGGACUUCACGCCUAUGUAUCGCUUCACACCAACGCUGCGCAGUACCACAGGGCAGAAAUGGGUGCUUGUGGUAUUCCAGCACAUAGGACUUCCUCCCCAGGAUGCAGUUACCCACACUGCUCACAUAUUUGCAUUUCUGUGGCCCCCUGUCAGCCUGAGUCUGCACUACGUGGUAAGCACUUGACAUUCGCCGUCUCAUUUCCCCAACUCCACUCGCACUUCCCCUUUCUGUGCAGGCUAAGGACAGAUUCAGGUUACCGGAGGGAAACAACAUUUCAAUGAAUUUGUUAGUCGCCUUUAUCGCUAUCAAAGCCAAUCGUGACAAGUUUGUCUUUUAAUGCAGCAACCAGUACUCGCGCAUAAGCCUCAUAGAUUUACAGAGGCCAUUUUAGAAACACGACCGAAACUUAGGUUAAGUCAGCUUUGCCUAAGAUCACGCCACUCGCAAAACAGCUGAGGUUCGAACCCGCACUGGGAAGGCUCGGAAGACCCCAAUCUCCUAUCUCAAAUUCCCACUGCCGAAGCCCCACGGUUCUCUGCCUAUGCGAACCAUGCAAAUACAGCGGUCGUCGCGCCACAGGCCGUGCUAGCCGCCAGCCCAGCCCCAUCUAGCCACCGCCUCCGGGAGAGUGGCGUGCCGCGAGUCGCGGGUCCCAAGUGCCGUCCGCUCUGCCCUGCAGCGCGCGUGGGAACGCGGCGGCGGUGGCCUCUGGGCUGCCCACGGCGACCGCCUGCGCGCACGGGAGCGGGUUUCCGCUAUCCCCACCGUGGCCUCCUCCUCGCCGCCACCACCUUCCCACCCCCCGGCCCGCGCAGGGGCUGGCGUCCGGGAAGCGCGCGGCGAUGCUUCUUUUUCGCCCGGCACCGCUGCAGCCACCUCACAUCCGGGCGCGCGGCGGGGAAGGCGGCGCCGGGGCCAGGGUGCAGAGCAUUGUAGACCAAGGAGCCAUGGAUAGGAGAAGUAUGGGUGAAACAGAAAGUGGAGAUGCUUUCCUUGACCUGAAGAAGCCUCCUGCCUCCAAAUGCCCCCAUCGCUAUACAAAAGAAGAACUCUUGGAUAUAAAAGAACUCCCCCAUUCCAAACAGAGGCCUUCAUGCCUUUCUGAAAAAUAUGACAGUGAUGGUGUCUGGGACCCUGAGAAGUGGCAUGCCUCUCUCUACCCAGCUUCAGGGCGGAGCUCACCAGUGGAAAGUCUGAAGAAAGAGUUGGAUACAGACCGGCCUUCCCUGGUGCGCAGGAUAGUAGAUCCACGAGAGCGUGUGAAAGAAGAUGACUUAGAUGUUGUUCUCAGCCCUCAGAGACGGAGCUUUGGAGGGGGCUGCCACGUGACAGCCGCUGUUAGCUCCCGGCGCUCAGGAAGUCCAUUAGAGAAAGAUAGUGAUGGGCUUCGUCUGCUUGGUGGACGUAGGAUUGGCAGUGGGAGGAUAAUCUCUGCCCGGACCUUUGAGAAGGAUCACCGUCUUAGCGAUAAGGACCUGCGGGACUUGAGAGACAGAGACCGAGAGAGGGACUUCAAGGACAAGCGUUUCAGGAGAGAGUUUGGAGAUAGUAAGCGUGUCUUUGGUGAGCGUAGAAGAAAUGAUUCUUACACAGAAGAAGAACCAGAGUGGUUCUCUGCUGGACCCACAAGUCAGUCUGAAACCAUCGAACUGACUGGCUUUGAUGAUAAGAUACUAGAAGAAGAUCACAAAGGGAGAAAAAGAACAAGGCGACGGACAGCCUCUGUGAAGGAAGGUAUAGUAGAGUGCAAUGGAGGAGUGGCCGAAGAGGAUGAAGUGGAGGUCAUCCUUGCACAGGAGCCUGCGGCUGAUCAGGAAGUGCCAAGGGAUGCUGUCUUGCCUGAGCAGUCCCCAGGAGACUUUGACUUUAAUGAGUUCUUUAACCUUGAUAAGGUGCCAUGCUUGGCUUCGAUGAUAGAAGAUGUUUUGGGAGAAGGGUCAGUCUCUGCCAGUCGGUUCAGUAGGUGGUUCUCUAACCCGAGCAGAUCAGGAAGCCGAUCCAGCAGUCUUGGGUCAACACCACAUGAAGAGCUAGAGAGACUUGCAGGUCUGGAGCAAGCCAUCCUCUCUCCUGGACAGAACUCGGGGAAUUACUUUGCUCCUAUACCAUUGGAAGACCAUGCUGAAAAUAAAGUGGAUAUUUUAGAAAUGCUACAGAAAGCCAAAGUGGAUUUGAAACCUCUUCUUUCCAGCCUUUCUGCAAAUAAAGAAAAACUUAAAGAAAGCUCACAUUCAGGGGUUGUGCUUUCAGUGGAGGAGGUAGAAGCAGGUCUGAAGGGCUUGAAGGUUGACCAGCAAGUGAAGAAUUCAACUCCCUUCAUGGCAGAACACCUAGAAGAGACCUUGAGUGCCGUAACCAACAAUCGACAACUGAAGAAAGACGGAGACAUGACUGCGUUCAACAAGCUAGUGAGCACAAUGAAGGCAAGUGGGACUUUGCCUUCUCAGCCCAAAGUCAGCCGAAACCUUGAAAGCCAUUUGAUGUCCCCUGCUGAGAUUCCAGGCCAGCCUGUCCCUAAGAACAUCCUGCAGGAACUUCUGGGUCAACCAGUUCAGAGACCUGCUUCUUCCAAUCUUCUGAGUGGCCUUAUGGGGAGCUUGGAGCCUACAACAUCUUUACUGGGCCAAAGAGCACCCUCUCCUCCCUUGUCACAGGUGUUUCAAACUCGAGCAGCCUCAGCUGACUACCUUCGCCCAAGAAUACCAUCACCAAUUGGUUUCACACCAGGACCACAGCAGCUACUCGGAGAUCCAUUCCAAGGCAUGCGCAAACCCAUGAGCCCCAUCACAGCCCAGCAGAUGAGCCAGCUGGAGUUGCAACAGGCAGCUUUAGAAGGGCUGGCCUUGCCACAUGACCUUGCUGUACAGGCAGCAAACUUCUACCAGCCUGGUUUUGGCAAACCACAGGUGGACAGAACCAGAGAUGGAUUCAGAAACAGGCAACAGCGAGUGACCAAGUCACCAGCACCCGUGCAUCGAGGGAAUUCCUCUUCCCCUGCCCCUGCUGCCUCCAUCACAAGCAUGCUUUCUCCUUCCUUUACCCCUACCUCAGUGAUUCGUAAGAUGUACGAGAGCAAAGAGAAAAGCAAGGAGGAGCCAGCAUCUGGAAAAGCAGCUCUUGGUGACAGUAAAGAGGAUACUCAGAAGGCCAGUGAAGAAAACCUCCUGUCAUCCAGCUCUGUACCCAGUGCCGAUCGAGACUCUUCUCCCACUACAAAUUCCAAACUGUCAGCAUUACAGAGGUCUUCGUGUUCCACCCCACUGUCCCAGGCCAACCGUUACACCAAAGAACAAGAUUAUCGACCUAAAGCAACUGGGAGAAAAACACCCACCUUGGCAUCCCCAGUUCCUACAACACCUUUUCUCCGCCCUGUCCACCAAGUUCCCCUUGUCCCCCAUGUCCCUAUGGUUAGGCCUGCUCACCAGCUUCACCCAGGGUUGGUACAGAGGAUGCUGGCCCAGGGAGUACAUCCACAGCAUCUUCCAAGUUUGCUCCAAACUGGUGUGCUUCCUCCUGGGAUGGACUUGAGUCAUUUACAGGGAAUAUCUGGCCCCAUCCUGGGUCAGCCCUUUUACCCUUUACCUGCUGCUAGUCACCCUCUCUUAAACCCUCGUCCUGGAACACCUCUGCAUCUGGCAAUGGUGCAACAGCAGCUACAGCGCUCAGUUCUGCAUCCUCCAGGCUCUGGUUCCCAUGCAGCAGCUGUCAGCGUUCAGACAACCCCUCAGAACGUGCCCAGCCGGUCAGGCCUGCCCCACAUGCACUCCCAGCUGGAGCAUCGCCCCAGCCAGAGGAGCAGCUCCCCUGUGGGCCUUGCCAAAUGGUUUGGCUCAGAUGUGCUACAGCAACCCCUGCCCUCCAUGCCCGCCAAAGUUAUCAGUGUAGAUGAAUUGGAAUACCGACAGUGAGCAGGGCAGGCAGACUCAACUAAGCCCGGACCUGUGGUGGCACACUGGGCAGGACCCUGCUUCAUCUCGGGUUGGUUUAUGGGCUUUUACUUUGGAGCACUCUGUGUGAAGCUGUUUGGUGGAACCCAUGCAUCUGGUGUGGUCCGCAUUAUGAUGGAAGGAUCUUAACCAGUCGAGUGGAGUGUACAUUGUCUGAAUACAGGAUGCACAAUGUUGUCAAUCCUGGAAAUGGUCUUUCUUUUUUGUAAGAUAUGUGAAUGAAGUGUUGGUGUCCUCACCAAGAGGUGGCACCUAAGGGUUCUGAGGAAAUAAAUGUAUAGACCCUUAUGUACAGACCUGUGUAUAAACAACUUUUGUAUAUACAUAUAGGAUAGCUUUUUUGAACUAUACAGCUGUACAUAAAAGUAGCUGAUAUUAGUUAGGCCUGUGUCAACAGUUUGGAUUUUUUUCACUUGUACAUUUGGGAUUUUCUUUUGGUUGAUUAAAAUUGCAUAUGCUAAGUGUGUGAAUGAA